ACACCAGCCGCAGGAGGCGCCGCACCUACUUCCCAAUAUAACCAACUACGGCGUGGGGGAGCGGAACUGCGAGAAGGCGGCAGCCAAAGUGCCAUUAAAGCUCGGGGCGGAGAGGAUGCGUUACCUGGGUCCCGUCUGCUGCGAGAGGCAGGGCAAGCUGGAGGAUUCCCUCUGAAUGAUUAAGAACUCCGCAAUUCGCCUCUGCCACAGGCUGCAAAGGACCCGAGGAACCGCUCUCUCUGAACUGUGCUGAUGGGCAGGAGGAUGGGAGACAGGAAUUGAGAGUCACAGAGGAAGGACAGUGGAGUCUGGCAUCUUAUUGGAGCCUCAGCAAAUAAAUGGCCUAAACAAUUGGAAGCCUAGGGAUGUAAUUGCUGGUCUUCUAUUAAAAAGUGAAGGAGACAAGAUUUUAAUGAAGGUGUCUUUAAAGGAUUGCCAUUUAAUGCCAUUCAAGAUCUACUAAGCAUCAUUUUUGCAUGACUACUGCAAAAGGAUUACUUUACAGAUACCAGUUCCUUUGUCAAGAGCAUACUUUGGACCCUGUUUUCAGAAAGCAGGGCACUCUUUAAUGAAGAAACACCAGAGCUGUUAAACACAUUGAGACACAGAAGAUUCUAGUGACUGAGGAUGGCUUCCUCUUGGAAACUAAUGCUGUUUCUGUCAGUCACCAUGUGUCUUUCAGAGUAUUCAAAAUCUCUUCCUGGUCUCUCCACUUCAUAUGCUGCUUUGUUAAGAAUUAAGAAGAGUUCAUCUUCAUCUCUCUUUGGUUCCAAAACCAGACCACGAUACAGCAGCCCUUCAUUAGGAACACUGAGUGCUUCUUCACCCAGCUGGCUAGGGGCAGCUCAGAAUUAUUAUUCCCCCAUCAAUCUUUAUCAUUCCUCAGAUGCCUUCAAACAAGAUGAAAGUGUGGACUAUGGGCCAGUUUUUGUGCAAGAACCAGAUGAUAUUAUUUUUCCAACUGAUUCUGAUGAAAAGAAGGUAGCAUUGAAUUGUGAAGUUCGUGGCAAUCCAGUUCCCAGUUACAGAUGGCUUCGAAAUGGAACAGAAAUAGAUCUGGAAAGUGAUUAUCGCUACAGUUUGAUAGAUGGCACCUUCAUUAUAAGCAAUCCAAGUGAAGCAAAGGAUUCUGGUCAUUAUCAGUGUUUAGCAACCAACACUGUGGGGAGUAUUCUUAGUAGAGAAGCUACACUGCAGUUUGCCUAUCUGGGAAAUUUUAGUGGCCGGACAAGAAGUGCAGUCUCUGUGAGGGAAGGCCAGGGUGUCGUUCUGAUGUGCUCUCCUCCGCCACAUUCACCAGAGAUCAUCUAUAGCUGGGUAUUUAAUGAGUUCCCUUCCUUUGUGGCGGAAGACAGCCGGCGGUUCAUCUCCCAGGAGACAGGCAACCUUUAUAUUUCUAAAGUCCAAACAUCAGAUGUUGGCAGCUAUAUUUGUCUGGUGAAAAACACAGUGACGAAUGCUAGAGUCCUUAGUCCUCCAACGCCACUCACUCUGCGUAAUGAUGGUGUGAUGGGAGAAUAUGAGCCGAAAAUUGAGGUCCAUUUUCCUUUCACGGUUACAGCUGCUAAAGGAACAACUGUUAAGAUGGAAUGCUUUGCACUUGGCAACCCCGUUCCAACAAUCACAUGGAUGAAGGUUAAUGGUUAUAUUCCUAGUAAGGCACGUCUGCGGAAAUCUCAGGCGGUGCUGGAAAUACCGAAUGUACAGCUGGAUGAUGCAGGCAUUUAUGAGUGCAGAGCUGAAAACUCACGUGGAAAAAAUUCCUUUCGUGGACAAUUACAAGUAUACACCUACCCACACUGGGUAGAAAAACUGAAUGAUACUCAGUUAGACAGUGGGAGCCCUCUCCGAUGGGAAUGUAAGGCUACUGGAAAACCCAGACCCACGUAUCGUUGGCUGAAGAAUGGAGUACCCCUCUCACCUCAGAGUAGGGUUGAGAUGGUUAAUGGAGUAUUGAUGAUCCACAAUGUGAAUCAAUCAGAUGCUGGAAUGUAUCAGUGUUUGGCUGAAAAUAAGUAUGGAGCCAUUUACGCUAGUGCUGAGCUGAAGAUUCUAGCUUCAGCUCCCACUUUUGCACUGAAUCAACUGAAGAAAACAAUAAUUGUUACCAAAGACCAAGAAGUUGUCAUAGAGUGCAAACCCCAAGGCUCUCCAAAACCAACCAUCUCUUGGAAGAAAGGAGACAGAGCAGUUAGAGAAAACAAAAGAAUAGCUAUUCUUCCAGACGGGAGUCUACGGAUCCUAAAUGCUUCCAAAUCAGACGAGGGAAAGUACGUUUGCCGAGGGGAAAACGUCUUUGGUUCUGCUGAAAUUAUAGCUUCGCUAUCUGUAAAAGAACCUACAAGGAUAGAACUUACUCCUAAAAGAACAGAAUUGACAGUGGGAGAAAGCAUUGUCCUUAAUUGCAAAGCAAUUCACGAUGCUAGUUUGGAUGUCACUUUCUACUGGACUCUGAAAGGACAGCCUAUUGAUUUCGAGGAAGAGGGUGGACAUUUUGAAAGCAUCAGGGCCCAAGCAUCCUCUGCAGAUUUAAUGAUCAGGAACAUCCUUCUGAUGCAUGCUGGGAGAUAUGGCUGCAGGGUACAGACCACAGCAGACAGUGUGUCAGAUGAGGCAGAACUUCUUGUUAGGGGACCCCCAGGCCCACCUGGGAUAGUAAUUGUUGAGGAAAUAACCGAAAGUACGGCCACACUGUCCUGGAGCCCAGCAGCUGACAACCACAGCCCAAUCUCCUCCUACAACCUUCAAGCUCGCAGCCCAUUUUCCCUGGGCUGGCAAACAGUAAAGACAGUCCCAGAAAUCAUAACAGGGGACAUGGAGUCAGCCAUGGCUGUGGACCUAAAUCCCUGGGUGGAAUAUGAAUUUCGAGUGGUAGCCACCAACCCUAUUGGGACAGGAGAUCCAAGCACCCCAUCUCGAAUGAUCCGCACAAAUGAAGCAGUUCCGAAGACAGCACCCACCAAUGUAAGCGGAAGAAGUGGAAGAAGGCAUGAGUUAGUCAUUGCCUGGGAGCCAGUAUCUGAAGAGUUUCAGAAUGGGGAAGGCUUCGGCUAUAUUGUGGCUUUCAGACCCAAUGGAACACGUGGCUGGAAGGAAAAAAUGGUGACAUCCUCUGAAGCUUCCAAAUUCAUUUAUCGAGAUGAAAGUGUCCCUCCUCUUACUCCCUUUGAAGUGAAAGUUGGCGUUUAUAACAAUAAAGGAGAUGGGCCUUUUAGUCAAAUUGUGGUCAUCUGUUCAGCUGAAGGAGAACCCAGUGCUGCUCCCACAGAUGUCAAGGCGACAAGUGUGUCUGUGUCAGAGAUUCUUGUUGCAUGGAAACACAUUAAAGAGAGUCUAGGAAGACCACAGGGAUUUGAGGUUGGUUACUGGAAAGACAUGGAACAGGAAGAUACAGCAGAAACAGUCAAAACUAGAGGGAAUGAGUCUUUCGUCAUCCUAACAGGAUUAGAAGGAAAUACGUUAUAUCACUUCACAGUGAGGGCUUACAAUGGAGCUGGAUAUGGGCCACCUAGCAGUGAAGUGAGUGCAACCACCAAGAAAUCCCCUCCUAGUCAAGCACCUAGCAACCUCAGGUGGGAGCAGCAAGGCUCUCAGGUUUCUCUGGGCUGGGAACCCGUCAUACCAUUAGCCAACGAAUCUGAAGUUGUGGGUUACAAGGUUUUUUAUAGGCAAGAGGGUCACAGCAACAGCCAAGUUAUUGAAACACAGAAACUUCAAGCAGUAGUACCACUCCCAGAUGCUGGAGUCUAUAUUAUUGAAGUUCGAGCAUAUAGUGAAGGAGGAGAUGGAACAGCUAGUUCUCAAAUUAGGGUACCAUCAUAUUCAGGUGGAAAAAUCACAAGUGCACAGUCGACCCUUCACUCUCUCUCCACAUCUUCGUCAUCAGUCACCUUGCUCUUGGCAUUGAUGAUUCCUUCAACUUCCUGGUGAAAACUGCUGACUUAAUUUGCUUUUGUUUGCUUUAGCUUGGUAACAGCGGUGAAUAGAGUGUAGUGUAAGUGGAGAACCAGGAUCCUGAGAUGAGCUUGAGCUUUAAAAACUUGGGACUAUACAUGGUGAACUUACAGGAGGUUAGGGGGGAAAUAUUACUUAUCCAUCAGGUUUCUCUUUGGUUUUUGUAAACGGAGAGGACAGUUCUUAGUCCAGUAAAAAUAUGCAGAUUGUAUGUAAUGAAUUUUUGUAAACAAAGGUAAUUUCUGUCAAAUGUAUUCUUUACUUUUUUAAUAUGUUGGGAUUUUAUUUUAUAUCUGAUGACUCCGAGUGUGUGCCAUCCAUUUGUUAAGUAACUGGCCUUUAGCAGAUCUGUUUCAAAAACAAAUACAAAAAUGAGAAUGAAAAGUUUGCUUAAGACUAAGUCCAGUGUUUUUCAUUUUCCCUUUGGCUGAAUAUUUCAAUUGACAAACCAGCAGGACAUAUGAAAAAUGCUUCAGUGAUGUGGUCCAUUAUAAGAUAAGUACACAAAAAUUUUCUUGAAAAAUAUUGUAUGAUUGCAUAGUGAAAUAGCAAGAUUUGUCAAUAUGCUAUUCUAUAUGCACCCCUAGAGCAAGUCAUUAGGGUAGGGAAUAAGCCAUUUACAUUAGUGCAAGAUAGAAAGCGAGUCCAGAUGAAUUUCAGUGCUAUAGUUUUUCAUAAAGUACUAUGUUAUCUAGCAGCAAAUAUAAUAAAUAUUUAUUUUUAAUAACAAAAGAUGGUUUAACAUCACCAAAAAAUAUGAUCACUAAAAACUGCAGACAUGCUGGCAUGGGUGCUAACUUAAAAAUGAGAUGAAUAUGGGACAGAGCGUUUCCAUUUCUUUACCUACUGCCAAAACAGAUGUUGAAUUAGGUCCAAGGUUUUCUUCUAAUUGCAAAAUUUUGCAAAAAUUUUAAGGGCAAUGAAAAUUUGUUGUGCAAAUAAUUAUGCAUAGUCUGUAGAUUAAAAUGGUUCAAGUAUAACAAAUAAGUUUUGAUUUUUAAAAACAGUUCCAUGCAUCACAUACCACUGAUAAAAUCAACUAGUAAAAUAAAGACAGUCUUUCUUGGAUAAAUUGAAUUUUUAAUUAAGCUGUGGAAACAUGGCAUCAGUACAGGGAUUCAGCUAGUCUAGCCAGCUAUGCACUGUUUGAUUCUGUGGCUUGGGAAGUAAUCCUUAUUUGCUAUUUCAAAGAGUCAUCUUGAGCCUGAGAGAUCCUAGAGAGUUGUUGGAAAAUGAGAUGAAAAUUUUCUACUUGAUGAUAUCUUAAAGAAGUUCUAACAAGCACAAGAAUGUGCCAGAGUUGGCAUCAUACCCAUGAAGAUGCGUGAAAGGAUAGUUAUUGCAAAGUCAUAUGCCAGAGAAGAGCCUGGAGAAACUAUGGUUUUAUAGGCGAUGUUAACAAGAGAACAAAAAUUGGUUUUAUAAUUUUAUAUAAUUUAAACUUGUUAACUGUAUUUGCUUCAUUAAUAACAAGCAAAAUGAAACAAUAUGGAGCUCAAAUUGCUAGCUCUCAAGGUUAAUCCUUGUAGAAUCAGAGAAGUGAUUGAAGUUUCUGUUCUGAACAUCCUGAAAGAAUAGUUUCAGAGCCACAGUAAAAGUCUGUAUGUAGGUUACAUAUUCUCUUUGGGGAAAUGAUGUAAGACACCCUAAACAAACAAGAAAUUAGUUAAAAGACUCACUCAAUGAUAUUAUAGUAAAUACUACAGAUGGUAAGUAUUUAAGCCUGUAAGUAAGUAAUUAUGACCAAGUGGCCUUUCUUGAACGCCUCCUUUAAAGUGGGAGAGGCUGGACUUUGCAAAAACAGGGAUGCUAAUUGUUUAGCUGGCAAAACAUGAGCUCUCCCAAGUAUAGUUUACCUUUAUGAAUUGUGCAUCUGAAUAAAAGACAGAAAGAAUAUUUUUAAUGCAAAAUAAUUUUACGUAUUUCAUGAAUCAAGCCAUUUUCUUCAUUUUCCAUGGUGGUGUACACCAGAUUUAGUGAAGGACUUUAAGAAUCAACUUCUUACUUACACUCUCAGAAAGCAAAGCCCAGUAAAAUAUUAAACAAAUAAAAUGGCAAAUUUAAAUUAACCAAUAUUUUUAAUUAGCUGAUGGAUGGUACGUAUCUGACAGAGUAUUUACACAUAUAGAAUGUCUGAUGUAUUCUUACAGGAAUCAGAGAUAUGGAAUGUUUUUACUUAACAUACACAGAAUAUGUAUUUUGCAUCAUAAACCUAUUUAAAAAACAGGUUUUCAAUGUUUAUGUACUUAUGUGCUGCAUAUCUGUUACUUUGUAGAAACCAGAAGAGCAUUCUUAUCAAGGUACAUUAUUUUUCAGCUACAGUACUGAGUUUUUUCUGCUAUGGGAUAGUAACCACAGUCUUAAAUCACUAAAGAGACUGUAUUUUUGUAUAAUGUCCAUUGAAUAUGAAGAAAGCAACAGUCCUUAUAAUUAGAAAUUUCAUGAAAGCAAAAGUUUUGCAUACCCAAAUGAAGGUACUGUGGACCCCAUGUCAAACUGUUAAAUAUAUUGUGUACGAUCUGUAUAUAUACUAUAUAUAAGGCAUAUACCGUGUGGAAGGCACAGUCAAAUAAUAGUUCUGUGUACUGUUCUUGUAACAUUAGAUCUUUUUAAUAAAUAAUUCUCUUUUUAUUGACUUUUA